CAUUGAGCCUUACCCCUUACUGGAGGCUGCAGGACCCUCUACACACAGACAGCUGUCCAGCACGGAAGGUGGGCUGAGGCCCAGGGUGAACAUGCCAGCUAAUGGGACAUCACCCCAGAGAUUCCCUGCCCUGAUUCCAGGAGAACCUGGCAGAUCUUUUGAGGGGUCCGUGUCAUUCGAGGAUGUGGCUGUGGAUUUCACCCGACAGGAGUGGCACAGACUGGACCCUGCUCAGAGGACCAUGCACAAGGAUGUGAUGCUGGAGACCUACAGCAACCUGGCAUCUGUGGGCCUCUGCGUGGCCAAACCAGAGAUGAUCUUCAAGUUGGAGCGAGGAGAAGAGCUGUGGAUAUUAGAGGAGGAAUCCUCAGGCCAUGGUUACUCAGGAUCUCUCUCACUGCUGUGUGGCAAUGGUUCUGUUGGGGAUAAUGCCCUCAGGCAUGAUAAUGACCUUCUUCACCAUCAGAAGAUUCAAACAUUGGAUCAAAAUGUUGAAUAUAAUGGAUGCAGGAAAGCCUUCCAUGAGAAAACAGGCUUUGUUAGACGUAAAAGAACACCCAGAGGAGAUAAAAACUUUGAAUGUCAUGAAUGUGGGAAAGCUUACUGUAGGAAGUCAAACCUUGUUGAACAUCUGAGAAUACACACAGGAGAGAGACCCUAUGAAUGCGGUGAAUGUGCAAAAACCUUCAGUGCAAGAUCAUACCUCAUUGCUCAUCAGAAAACUCACACAGGGGAGAGGCCCUUUGAAUGUAAUGAAUGUGGGAAAUCUUUUGGCAGGAAGUCACAACUCAUCCUACAUACAAGAACACACACUGGAGAGAGACCCUAUGAAUGUACUGAAUGUGGGAAAACCUUUUCUGAGAAGGCAACCCUCACGAUUCAUCAGAGAACUCACACAGGGGAGAAACCCUAUGAAUGUAGUGAAUGUGGGAAAACAUUUCGUGUAAAGAUAUCCCUUACCCAACACCACAGAACUCAUACAGGGGAGAAACCUUAUGAAUGUGGGGAGUGUGGGAAAAACUUCCGUGCAAAGAAAUCCCUAAAUCAGCAUCAAAGAAUUCACACAGGUGAGAAACCCUAUGAGUGUGGUGAAUGUGGGAAAUUCUUCCGAAUGAAGAUGACUCUCAAUAAUCAUCAAAGAACUCACACAGGUGAAAAGCCCUAUCAGUGUAAUGAAUGUGGGAAAUCUUUCAGGGUGCACUCAUCUCUUGGGAUCCAUCAGAGAAUUCACACAGGAGAGAAACCUUACGAAUGUAAUGAGUGUGGUAAUGCUUUCUAUGUGAAAGCACGCCUAAUUGAACAUCAGAGGAUGCAUUCAGGAGAGAAACCCUACGAAUGUAGUGAAUGUGGGAAAAUCUUCAGUAUGAAGAAAUCCCUUUGUCAACACCGGAGAACUCACACAGGAGAGAAACCUUAUGAAUGUAGUGAAUGUGGAAAUGCCUUCUAUGUGAAAGUACGCCUCAUUGAACAUCAGCGAAUUCACACAGGAGAGAGACCCUUUGAGUGUCAAGAAUGUGGGAAAGCUUUCUGCCGGAAAGCACACCUCACAGAACAUCAGAGAACUCACAUAGGCUGGUCCUGGCGUUGUACAAUGAAGAAAGCCUCUCACUGAAGACUUCCCUCACCAUUGGAUCAAGCUCCUUGGGGGCAUAUGAUCACCAGGGCACACAGUGUGCCUGUGAAAAUUUGGCACCUACAUUUGUAUCAAAGUAUGUCCUGAUCCCCUUAGGGGAUAGCUCAUUGUUUUUAUUCAGAUUUCCCUAAUUAGUGGUGUGUGAACAUCUUAUCUGUUGAUUGGCUAUUUGGGUUUUUUCUUCUGUGCAUUGACUGUUCAUGUCCUCUGCUCAUUGUUUUCAAAUGGGCUGUUCAUCUCUUGCUUUUUGGUUUAAAUGUUGUUUUUUAACAUAUGAGAAUAUAAAAAUCCUUUUUUUUUCAGUCAUAUGUGUUGCAAAUAUCUUCUCCCAGACUGUCGUUGGUUUUUUAAAUUUUGCCAUCUGUUUUCUUCUGCUGAAGUUUUAUAUUUUAUUUAUUUAUUUUUUAUUUUUUUGAGAUGGAGUCUCACUCUGUCACCCAGGCUGGAGUGCAAUGGCAUGACCUCAGCUCAUUUCAACCUUCGCCUCCCGGGUUCAAGCGAUUCUCCUGCCUCAGUCUCCCAAGUAGCUGGGAUUACAGGUGUGCACCACCAUGCCUGGCUAAUUUUUGUAUUUUUAGUAAAGACGGGGUUUCACCAUGUUGGCCAGGCUGGUCUCUAACUCCUGACCUCAGGUGAUCCACCUGCCUCGGCCUCCAAAAGUGUUGGGAUUACAGGUGUGAGCCACCGUGCCCGGCUAAAGUUUUAUAUUUUAAUAUUAUCAGUUUCAAGGUGAUAAUAUUCACCUAUACUUUCCUCUAAAGGUUUUCCUUUCAACAUUUAGAAUUUUAAUCUCCUGUGAGAUUUUUUUGUUAUAGCAUGAAGUGUGCAAUACAUACUACUAUAUUGUCUUUAUAUAAUUUUACAUAAAUGGGCUCACACUGUA